CCCGCUGCUCUGCUGCCUGCCCGGGGUACCAACAUGGCCCAGAAGCGUCCUGCCUGCACCCUGAAGCCUGAGUGUGUCCAGCAGCUGCUGGUUUGCUCCCAGGAGGCCAAGAAGUCAGCCUACUGCCCCUACAGUCACUUUCCUGUGGGGGCUGCCCUGCUCACCCAGGAGGGGAGAAUCUUCAAAGGGUGCAACAUAGAAAAUGCCUGCUACCCGCUGGGCAUCUGUGCUGAACGGACCGCUAUCCAGAAGGCCGUCUCAGAAGGGUACAAGGAUUUCAGGGCAAUUGCUAUCGCCAGUGACAUGCAAGAUGAUUUUAUCUCUCCAUGUGGGGCCUGCAGGCAAGUCAUGAGAGAGUUUGGCACCAACUGGCCCGUGUACAUGACCAAGCCGGAUGGUACGUAUAUUGUCAUGACGGUCCAGGAGCUGCUGCCCUCCUCCUUUGGGCCUGAGGACCUGCAGAAGACCCAGUGACAGCCAGAGAAUGCCCACUGCCUGUAACAGCCACCUGGAGAACUUCAUAAAGAUGUCUCACAGCCCUGGGGACACCUGCCCAGUGGGCCCCAGCCCUACAGGGACUGGGCAAAGAUGAUGUUUCCAGAUUACACUCCAGCCUGAGUCAGCACCCCUCCUAGCAACCUGCCUUGGGACUUAGAACACCGCCGCCCCCUGCCCCACCUUUCCUUUCCUUCCUGUGGGCCCUCUUUCAAAGUCCAGCCUAGUCUGGACUGCUUCCCCAUCAGCCUUCCCAAGGUUCUAUCCUGUUCCGAGCAACUUUUCUAAUUAUAAACAUCACAGAACAUCCUGGA